AGACUCGAGCAGUCUCUGGAACACGCUGCGGGGCUCCCGGGCCUGAGCCAGGUCUGUUCUCCACGCAGGUGUUCCGCGCGCCCCGUUCAGCCAUGUCGUCCGGCAUCCAUGUAGCGCUGGUGACUGGAGGCAACAAGGGCAUCGGCUUGGCCAUCGUGCGCGACCUGUGCCGGCUGUUCUCGGGGGACGUGGUGCUCACGGCGCGGGACGUGACGCGGGGCCAGGCGGCCGUACAGCAGCUGCAGGCGGAGGGCCUGAGCCCGCGCUUCCACCAGCUGGACAUCGACGAUCUGCAGAGCAUCCGCGCCCUGCGCGACUUCCUGCGCAAGGAGUACGGGGGCCUGGACGUGCUGGUCAACAACGCGGGCAUCGCCUUCAAGGUUGCUGAUCCCACACCCUUUCAUAUUCAAGCUGAAGUGACGAUGAAAACAAAUUUCUUUGGUACCCGAGAUGUGUGCACAGAAUUACUCCCUCUAAUAAAACCCCAAGCAUCCUGCGUACUGUCUGCAUGGUCAUGCCUCUCCCAAAAUCCUUCAGGAGGAAAGUCCAAGCCCUUAGCAUGGUUCACAGAGAUGUCCAUAAUCUGCCGCUGCUUAACUCUGGGCCCAUUUUAACUCCCCUUCAACGUGCUGAAGGUGCUGGACAUGACUAUCACAUGUCUUUGGUUGUAAACUGCUGUGAUAGUUACCCUAAGUAAUGGGACAGGAGAUGAACCCACCCAUUAAAUAACACAGCAAUUAAGCAGCCACUUUUAGAAAAAUUUAAAUGUGUGGCUUCGAGUUGGGUACUUGCAUGUACAGCUUACUCUCAGCUUUUAUCCUGUUUCCCUGUCCUGUCGUCCUGUUAAGUUGUGCUACUUCUAAGGCUCUGGUUCACCAGGACCUCAAAGGGCAGCUCUUCCAAAUCUCACCUGACUCUACUCAGCCAAAAUUCGAAGGCAGGAAUGAACUUCUUCAUGCAACUACCACCACACUUUCUAUGCGUAUUCCUCUUAGAACUCAUACCAGUAACUGUCUCUCAUAUGAAAAUUUUCUGCUCCAAAAUCCCUGCAAAUUUGGCAUUCACCUCUCUACGGGAUUGUUGCACACCUUUCUACAUAAUGCUUUGUGGUGUAUCUUAGGGAGAGUGGUGAACGUAUCUAGCAUCAUGAGCGUCAGAGCCCUUAAAAGCUGCAGCCCAGAGCUGCAGCAGAAGUUCCGCAGUGAGACCAUCACUGAGGAGGAGCUGGUGGGGCUCAUGAACAAGUUUGUGGAGGAUACAAAGAAGGGAGUGCACCAGAAGGAGGGCUGGCCCAGCAGCGCAUACGGGGUGACGAAGAUUGGCGUCACCGUUCUGUCCAGGAUCCACGCCAGGAAACUGAGUGAGCAGAGGAAAGGGGACAAGAUCCUCCUGAAUGCCUGCUGCCCAGGGUGGGUGAGAACUGACAUGGCGGGACCCAAGGCCACCAAGAGCCCAGAAGAAGGUGCAGAGACCCCUGUGUACUUGGCCCUUUUGCCCCCAGAUGCUGAGGGUCCCCAUGGACAAUUUGUUUCAGAGAAGAGAGUUGAACAGUGGUGAGCUGGGCUCACAGCUCCAUCCAUGGGCCCCAUUUUGUACCUUGUCCUGAGUUGGUCCAAAGGGCAUUUACAAUGUCAUAAAUAUCCUUAUAUAAGAAAAAAAAUGAUCUCUUAUCAAUUAGCACUCACUAAUGUACUACUAAUUGAGCAACCUACGCACUCAGUUGACUACGUAAAUCUGUCAGGUCUUUUGUGAUUUCCUCUGAUGCAGGAGAGGAAAAAUUGUAAUUGAUGAAAAUAAUGAAUGAAAAUCAACAGAUGAAUAAAUGGUUCUUUAUAAGUG